GUGGAGUCGCAAAAGCUGAACAUCCUCCCCACAAGGUUAUUUAGAAGACGUCUUGCACUGUUCAAAUGCAGAGGAAGGCGAAUGACUCGAGUCUAUGGUUUUGGUAUACUGAGCCUGGGGCUACUGGUGUCAGCCUGGUGGUAGUGCAGCUCAUCUGAUGCCUGGGGCUGCAGGAUCCUAGUUGGUUCCUGUGACAGACCUUGGGAAGCUCAAUCUCAGGAAAAAGAAGAGAGAGCCAACUACUCUACAAAGGAAAAGGGAUGUAGUUUGUAGGAUUUUCCUUGUUAUGAGAGGAGCAGAAACCUAACUGUUGACAAGGAUGUGUUUUCUUAAUUGAAGAAAAUCAUAUCACAUGUGAACUUUCUGACCAUACUGUGGAGCGGUGCUAAUAAGGAGGGUUCUGUGUUCACUUGACUACCAGAAACAUUUCUAGUUUACCAUCAGAGUUUUAGCCGCUUCCAUGCUUCUGUGACUGCAGCUACUCUCAGGAAGCUGCACUGUUGCAGAGGUCCAUUAACUCUUUCAGGACGGUGUGGAAUCAGUGGGGAAAUCUCUAAUUGCUACUGACACAGAGUACAUUACCUUCAAGCAAAACACUGAGAGGCUUCUAAAAACUAUUUUGCUUAAGGAGGAUCACUUUUGCUCAUGGUUCUCUAAUAAGAACAUUUUCCAAGGUGCAGCAAGUUUCGAUCUUCAAAAACCCGCAGCUACUCACAGUGUAAGAUGCCUGUCGGGGUGGGGCUCUGGGCCUGGAAAAACUAGAGCAGUCUGGAUGCUGCGAGGCGGCGAGCAGAGCUUUUAGGGGCCUGGCCUUUGCAGUUCCAGAUCUACUACAGCAAACAUCGUUCAAGAUGUCCCACCAAGAAGGCAGCACAGACGGCUUACCAGACUUAGGGACUGAAAGCCUGUUCAGCAGCCCAGAGGAGCAGUCUGGAGCCGUGGCGGCGACAGAGGCCUCCUCAGACAUUGACAUAGCGACCUCAGAGCUGAGUGUGACAGUGACCGGAGAUGGCAGUGAUAGCAGGGAUGGUGGAUUCCCCAACGAUGCCAGCACAGAAAAUCGAAGCUCAGACCAAGAAAGCGCAAGUGAAGACAUCGAACUUGAGAGCUUGGAGGACUUUGAGCAUUUCCUCAUGAGUGGUGAAAGUUUAUUCCAUUACCCUUUAGUGGGAGAGGAGGAGACAGAAAGGGAGGAGGAAGACGAAGAGAUACAAGAGGAGGGAGGGGAGGAGGAGGAAGAGGAGGAGGAGGAGGAGGAGGAGGAGGAGGAGGAGGAGGAGGAGGAAGAAGAACAGCCUCGGGCGGGUCCACAAGGCAGUGGCGGCAACCAUGAGCAGUAUUCGUUAGAGGAGGAUCAGGCGCUGGAGGAGUGGGUUUCCUCAGAGACAUCUGCCCUGCCCCGACCUCGCUGGCAGGUCGUUACUGCUCUUCACCAGCGGCAGCUGGGUUCACGUCCCCGCUUUGUAUAUGAGGCCUGUGGGGCAAGAGCCUUUGUGCAGCGUUUCCGCCUGCAAUAUCGUCUUGCAGACCAUGUCGGCUGUGUCAAUACUGUACACUUUAACCAGCGUGGCACCCGGCUGGCCAGUAGCGGUGAUGACCUAAAGGUGAUAGUGUGGGACUGGGUGCGGCAGAGGCCAGUACUGAACUUUGAAAGUGGUCACACAAAUAAUGUCUUCCAGGCCAAGUUCCUUCCUAACUGUGGUGAUUCCACUCUGGCCAUGUGUGCCCGUGAUGGGCAGGUACGGGUAGCAGAGUUAAUUAAUGCAUCAUAUUUCAACAAUACUAAGUGUGUGGCCCAGCACAGGGGACCUGCCCACAAGUUGGCUCUGGAGCCUGACUCUCCUUAUAAGUUCCUCACUUCAGGUGAAGAUGCUGUUGUCUUCACCAUUGACCUCAGACAAGACCGGCCAGCUUCAAAAGUUGUGGUAACAAGAGAAAAUGAUAAGAAAGUGGGACUGUAUACAAUUACUGUGAAUCCCGCCAAUACCUACCAAUUUGCAGUGGGUGGACAAGAUCAGUUUGUAAGGAUUUAUGACCAGAGGAAAAUUGAUAAGAAAGAAAACAAUGGCGUGCUCAAGAAAUUCACUCCUCAUCAUCUGGUUAAUUGUGAUUUCCCAACAAACAUCACCUGCGUUGUGUACAGCCACGAUGGCACAGAGCUGCUAGCCAGCUACAAUGAUGACGAUAUUUACCUCUUCAACUCCUCUCACAGUGAUGGUGCUCAAUACAGUAAGAGAUUUAAGGGACACAGAAAUAAUACCACAGUCAAAGGUGUUAAUUUCUAUGGCCCCAGGAGUGAGUUUGUAGUGAGCGGUAGUGAUUGCGGGCACAUCUUCUUCUGGGAGAAAUCAUCCUGCCAAAUCAUCCAGUUCCUAAAGGGGAGCAGAGAAGGUACAAUAAACUGUCUUGAACCCCACCCUUACCUACCUGUGUUGGCGUGCAGUGGCCUAGAUCAUGAUGUCAAGAUCUGGACACCCACAGCUAAAGCUGCCACUGAGCUUACUGGGUUAAAGAAGGUGAUUAAGAAGAACAAGUGGGAACGAGAUGAAGACAGCUUGCACCAUGGCAGCCUGUUUGACCAGUACAUGCUUUGGUUCCUCCUGCGUCACGUGACGCAGAGAGGUCGUCACCAGGACUGGAGAAGUGGUGAAGCUGAAUUUCCAGAUGAAGAAUCGGAUGAGUCUUCCAGCACUUCAGAGACAUCUGAGGAGGAGGUCCAAGACCGAGUGCAGUGCAUGCCAUCCUGAAGGCCUCAUAUCCAGUCCAGCUACAUGCCACCUAAGUACACUGGACUUUAAAAUUCAGUUUGACUAAUUUAGAAUUGUCAAUAGAUUAAUAGAUUUGCUUUUUGUCUUCUAUUUUCCAUAAUAUAUGCUGAAAACCGUCUCUUCCAUUCCUUCCUCUCUACUUUCCUUUCUUUCUUCCACACAUUCUUUCUCUCAUUCCUUUCCUCUUGGUUUCUUUACGCCUCUUUUGUUACCCCUUAUUCUUACAUGAGUGCAUACACAACUUAUUUAUGCCUCUUUUCCUUUGUUCCCUUAUAGUUGACCUCUAAAUUUUCUGAAUUUUGCUGAAAGAAUUAAUACCCUUAUUAGAUGCAUCUACUCAAAUCUGACAGUCUGAAAACGGUUACCUUUUUACUUUUUUUCAUCUUUAACAAUUUUUUCUGAAGAUCGAGUUCCUCAGUUGACCUGAAAAUUUCAGAAAUGUGUUUCUUCUUUAGAAAAUAAGACAAACUACAGUUUUGUUCUGUCGAUACUGACACUUGGCCGCACACACACAGUCUCAGAAAAGGAAAAGAGAAGUAGUGUGUAGAUUAAUUCUUAACACUUGGCCAUACGCAGACACAGUCUCAGAAAAGGAAAAGAGGAGAGGUACUAUGUAGAUUAAUUCCUAACCAGAUAAUUCAUCUCCUUAGAAUAAAUAACGUGGGAUUGCCUACAUUUUCUGAAUCCAUAUAUUAAUAAUUUUGAAAAAUUUGAGUACACUGUAGCUGGUAAGAACUAAAUUAAAUUUGAUCACAUGACAUUGUUUACUCUGUGCAUUAAGUUUUCUUGAAGUUUUAAGGUUGGGAACUCCCACAGGGUUACCUUCCAGGAAGUCCUCCUGGGACAAGCAUGUCCUAUAAAUGCCAGCUUACUGAUAUAAAAAUCUCUCAUAUUUGAAAACGCAUUCUAAUUAACUUUUAAGAACAAGUUGCAAUAAAGAUUGUUUAUACUUACACAUAACCAUUUGGUGUAAUUGGUAGAAAAAUCCUAUUUGACAUCCUCACAUUGCUUAAAAUUCUCUCUGCUGUUUAAAUUGCUUUAAAAAUUGUUUUAUGCCUCAUUUAAUAUAAAUUAAAUAAGGGUACUGGAUGUCCAAUUACUGCUCAAUAAAAAUAUUUGUUUUUAUUUUA